GCCCCUCCGAGAACCGCCAAGUUGGUACCAGCCCCUGCCGGCUGCCCUCGGUUUCCUAGGUAGGUGUUGGGAUCCGCCACGCGCGUGGGGGCCGUCGGAAGCCCACCCCUGCGGUGAUCAGGUUUUAGGACCAGUCCAAAUCUUGGAUAUGGGAGAGUCAAAACGUCAACUUUGGGUUGUGUCCUGUCGGAGUCAGUGGGGGAGUAGUUUAGCUUCUUAUAUCCUCAGUGGGCUGCCACAUCCUCUCCCCUCCCCCCAGAAAGAUAGCUAAAUAAACUUUAAAUUCCUCAGCCCCAUUGCCCCAAUCCCCACUUCCAAACCAGAUUGCCAGGGACAGCACCUGCUAGGUGGAAGUUCUGAGAACGUUGCGCUGGAGAAUUCACGCCUGAAAGCCUAGCCCUUGGGAGCUAGAGGCCUGAACUGGGCGGAUACGUGCCCAUGUGUACAGUUUCUGUGAUUUUAAAAUUCUGAAUCCUUUAAAUCUUAGGAAACAAGCUGGAUUUAAAGUACCUCCUUAUCUAUUUUUCUUGAAUCAUGAGAGAUGAAAUUGCAACAACAGUUUUCUUUGUCACAAGAUUGGUGAAAAAACAUGAUAAACUAAGUAAACAGCAAAUAGAAGACUUUGCAGAAAAGCUGAUGACGAUCUUGUUUGAAACAUACAGAAGUCACUGGCACUCUGAUUGCCCUUCUAAAGGGCAAGCCUUCAGGUGCAUCAGGAUAAACAACAAUCAGAAUAAAGAUCCCAUUCUAGAAAGGGCAUGUGUGGAAAGUAAUGUAGAUUUUUCUCACCUGGGACUUCCGAAGGAGAUGACCAUAUGGGUAGAUCCCUUUGAAGUAUGCUGUAGGUAUGGUGAGAAAAACCAUCCAUUUACAGUUGCUUCUUUUAAAGGCAGAUGGGAGGAAUGGGAACUAUAUCAACAAAUCAGUUAUGCCGUUAGUAGAGCCUCAUCAGACGUUUCCUCUGGCACUUCCUGCGAUGAAGAAAGUUGUAGCAAGGAACCUCGUGUCAUUCCUAAAGUCAGCAAUCCGAAGAGUAUUUAUCAGGUUGAAAACUUGAAACAGCCCUUUCAAUCUUGGUUACAAAUCCCCCGCAAAAAGAAUGUGGUGGACGGCCGUGUUGGCCUCCUGGGAAACACUUACCAUGGCUCGCAGAAGCAUCCUAAGUGUUACAGGCCUGCUAUGCACCGGCUGGACAGGGAAACAAUUCCAAGAAAAAGGACAUUCUUCACCCAGCAGCUCCUGCCAUAUUCACUGAGAUGUGUUUUUGUAUUUUCCUAUGUAUUUCUUCAUCAGAGAUGCCCUAAAGCCUGGAAUAGAACUUGGCACAAUUACAUGAUGCUGGAAUGCAGUGGCACGAUUACAGCUCACCUUGACCUCCUGGGCUCCAGCAAUCCUCCAACCUCCACCUUCAAGUAGCUGGGACUACAGGCACAUGCCACCAUGCCUGGCUAAUUUUUAAAUUUUUUUGUGGAAAUGGGGUCUCACUAUGUUGUCUAGGCUGGUCUUGAACUUUUGGGCUCAAGCGAUCCUCCCACCUUGGCCUCCCAAAGUGCUGGGAUUGCAGGUGUAAGCCAAUACACUGGGCCAGCAACUCGUUCUUAAAGGGAAUUUGUUUACAAUUUCCCUAUUAUGUAUAACAUCACUCUAGAUUUUUGGCAUAUAAACUUUAUCAAGUUAAGGAAGUUUCCUUCUAGUCCUAAGUUUCUAAGAGUUAUUUUUCUUAAAUUACAAAUAGAUGUUGGACUUUAUCAAAUGUUUAGAUAUUUGAUUGAGAUACUUUAAUAAUUUUUCUCCUAAAGUUUAUCAAUGUGGUGAAUUAUAUUGAUAGGUUUUCUAAGAAUAAACCAUCCUUGCAUUCCUGGGAUAAAUCUUACAUAUUAUAAUAUAUUAUUAUUAUAUCAUGAUGUAUUAGUCCUUAAUAUACUAUUGAAUUCAGCAAGCAAAUAUUUUGUUCAGGAUUUUUGAAUCGAUGUUCACAAAUUAGAUGGCCUAUAAUUUUCUUUUCUUAUAUUGACCUUAUUUAGUUUUAGAAUCAAGUUUACAUGAUUGGCUCUUUAAAGUAAUUUAAAUUAAAUGCAGAAAUCUGUCUUUUAAUUGGUGAGUUUAAUCUUCUUAAAUUCAUUAUCAUUACUGAGCUAGUUGAACCUAUCCUGCCAACUUAUUCCUGUUUUCCAUUCAUUGUAAUUUUUAAAUACAUCCUUCCUGUUUUUCACAGAAAGAUUCAGUUUCUCUCAGAAUGCUCAAAAGUUAAAUGUUUAAAAUUUAAAAGCUAAACUUUGAAACAUUAAAAGUUAAACAGAAUGUUUAACACAUCAUUUAUGAAAAAGUUAAACAGAAUGUUUAAAAGUUUAACUUUUGUUUUAUUUUUUGUUAUAAAAAAAUUUUUUUUUGUAAUAAGAACAAAAGUGGCAGUUGCCUCCUACUUCAGAUCCACUUUUAUGUUUAUUUGUCCUUCAGAUCCACUUUUAUGUUUAUUUGUCCCUAUUGAUUUCUUAAAUUUAUUGAUAGCUAUAUUUUCUCCUUAGAAAACGAAAGCAUUAGUGCAUUUUGAUUUCUCUUUGAUCUCCUUAAGGGCCACAUUUUGGAAAAUUAAAUAUAAUAUAAAUGGUGUUCUCUGGACUUGUGUAAUCAUGUUAUUUUAAAGAUAUUUUGUUUUGUGUUGUUAUGGAUGAAUUUUCUCCUUUUCCCAGCUUUAAGAAAAUUCCUAUAAUAAACUUUACCCAGUAUUUGAUUA